GUCUCCGAACCUGAAACCGGGAGCUUCCUGCUCGUGUUCGCUGUUGAGAAGCUACCCGCGGGGUUGUAGACCUCGGACCUCAUGGCAGAGAUAAUUCAGGAACGCAUAGAAGAUCGGCUCCCGGAAUUGGAACAGCUGGAGCGCAUUGGACUGUUCAGUCAUGCGGAGAUUAAGGCUAUCAUUAAGAAGGCUUCCGAUCUAGAGUACAAAAUCCAGAGAAGAACCCUUUUCAAGGAAGACUUUAUCAAUUAUGUUCAAUAUGAAAUUAAUCUUUUGGAGCUGAUCCAGAGAAGAAGAACACGCAUUGGAUAUUCAUUUAAGAAGGAUGAGAUUGAGAAUUCUAUUGUACACCGGGUACAAGGUGUUUUCCAGCGUGCCUCAGCAAAAUGGAAAGACGAUGUUCAACUUUGGCUCUCCUAUGUGGCUUUUUGUAAGAAGUGGGCUACUAAAACUCGACUUAGCAAGGUAUUCUCUGCCAUGUUGGCGAUUCAUUCCAACAAACCAGCUUUGUGGAUUAUGGCAGCCAAAUGGGAAAUGGAAGAUCGAUUGUCUUCAGAAAGCGCAAGGCAACUAUUUCUUCGCGCACUGCGCUUUCAUCCAGAGUGCCCAAAACUUUAUAAAGAAUACUUUAGGAUGGAGCUGAUGCAUGCUGAAAAACUGAGGAAGGAGAAGGAAGAAUUUGAAAAAGCCAGUAUGGAUGUGGAGAAUCCUGAUUAUUCUGAAGAAAUCCUUAAGGGCGAGUUGGCAUGGAUCAUCUACAAAAAUUCUGUAAGCAUAAUUAAAGGUGCAGAAUUUCACGUGUCACUGCUUUCGAUUGCACAGCUAUUUGACUUUGCCAAAGAUCUACAAAAAGAGAUUUAUGAUGACCUUCAGGCUCUACACACAGAUGAUCCUCUCACUUGGGAUUAUGUGGCAAGGCGAGAAUUAGAGAUUGAGUCACAGACAGAAGAGCAGCCUACAACGAAACAAGCCAAAGCAGUGGAGGUCGGCCGGAAGGAGGAGAGGUGCUGUGCUGUGUAUGAAGAGGCAGUGAAGACUCUGCCAACAGAGGCCAUGUGGAAGUGUUACAUCACCUUUUGCUUGGAAAGAUUUACUAAGAAGUCAAAUAGUGGGUUCCUUAGAGGGAAGAGGUUGGAAAGAACCAUGACUGUAUUCAGGAAGGCACAUGAACUGAAGCUUCUGUCAGAAUGCCAAUACAAGCAGUUGAGUGUUUCGUUGCUGUGUUAUAACUUCCUGAGGGAAGCUCUGGAAGUGGCAGUAGCUGGAACUGAAUUGUUUAGAGACUCUGGGACAAUGUGGCAGCUGAAGCUGCAGGUGCUGAUCGAGUCAAAGAGCCCUGACAUAGCCAUGCUUUUUGAAGAAGCCUUUGUGCACCUGAAACCCCAGGUUUGUCUGCCAUUGUGGAUUUCCUGGGCAGAGUGGAGUGAAGGUGCCAAAAGCCAAGAAGACACUGAGGCAGUCUUUAAGAAAGCUCUCUUAGCUGUCAUAGGUGCCGACUCAGUAACCCUGAAGAAUAAGUACCUGGAUUGGGCUUAUCGAAGUGGUGGCUACAAAAAGGCCAGAGCUGUGUUUAAAAGUUUACAGGAGAGCCGACCAUUUUCAGUUGACUUUUUCAGGAAAAUGAUUCAGUUUGAAAAGGAGCAAGAAUCCUGCAAUAUGGCGAACAUAAGAGAAUAUUAUGAGAGAGCUUUGAGAGAGUUUGGAUCCGCAGAUUCUGAUCUUUGGAUGGAUUAUAUGAAAGAAGAAUUGAACCACCCCCUUGGUAGACCUGAGAACUGUGGACAGAUCUACUGGCGAGCGAUGAAAAUGUUGCAGGGAGAGUCAGCAGAGGCAUUUGUAGCUAAACAUGCUAUGCAUCAGACUGGCCAUUUAUGAAGAUGAAGAAUACAGUCAGCUUUGUGAAAUAGUAUUGCAAGCAAGCCCCGUGGGCAAAUUUGUAUUGAGUCCAUCUGUAAUUUGCUCAGUGAUGGCAGACAAGAUGGCUGUCUGGUUUUGAGACACACUUUAAUUUUAUGUUAACUUGUUAAAUCUUUUUAAAAAUUAAAAAAUUUUUAUGAUUGAGACUGGGUCUUGCUCUGUUGCCCUGGCUGGUCUUGAACUCCUGGACUCAAGUGACCUUCUCACCUCAGACUCCUGAGUAGCUGGGAUUAUAGGUGCAUGACACUGCUCAGUUUGAUGUGCUAAUCUGAUUCCAGUAAAGAGAAUUGCUGAUUUAAUGUUGAGGCCCGAUCUUCCACAGGUCCUAAAUGUUUCCCAAAAUACAUGGAUAGCAUACGACUGGGUUUUUUUAAAAUUAUCCCAGGUCAAGCAUGAGUAUCUCUAAUCUCGACCUAAGAGCCAGUUAAAAUGAAGGAGAAAGUGGCCAGGCAUGGUGACUCAACGCCUGUAAUCCCAGCACUUUGGGAAGGCUGAGGCAGGCGGAUCACCUGAGGUCAGGAGUUUGAGACUAGCCUGGCCAACAUGGUGAAACCCCGUCUCUACUAAAAAUACAAAAAUUAGCCAGGUGUGGUGGUGGGUGCCUGUAAUCCCAGCUGCUUGGGAGGCUGAGGCAGGAGAAUUGCUUGAACCUGGGAGACGGAGGUUGCAGUGAGCCGAGAUCAUGCCAUUGCUACUCCAUCCUGGGUAAGAAGAGCGAAACUCCUUCUCAAGGAAAAAAAAAAAGGAGAAAGUACAGUUUUGUUGGUUUAUUCUCAUUAUAAAAGAUACGUGGUAUGCAUUUGUUCUGGAAAAUAUGGAGGAAAUAGAAUAGUGUGGUAAAAAAAAGCAUCCUGUCACUGGGAGAAGCUUUCAGUGUAGCUUAUUGUUACGUUUCACUUAGUAUUGUUUUUCUGUGUCAUUAAAUAGCCUUAAAAACAUUUAAUGAAUUCGUAACAUUACAUUGUAAAAAUGAGCCAUAAUAUAUUUUACUAAUCCUCUGGUUAGACUGUCUUUUUUUUUUUGAGAUGGAGCCUUGCUCUGUCAUCCAGGCUGGAGUGCAGUGGCUCCAUCUCGGCUCACUGCAACCUCCACCUCCCGGGUUCAAGUGGUUCUGGCUCAGCCUCCCGAGCAGCUGGGUGGGAUUACAGGCACCCGCCACCGCGCCCAGCCAAUUUUUGUAUUUUUAGUAGUGCGGGGGUUUCAUCAUAUUGGCCAGGCUGGUUGCGAACUCCUGACCUCAUGAUCCACCCGCCUUGGCCUCCCAAAGUGUUGGGAUUACAGGCGUGAACCACUAAGCCUGGCCUGGACUGUCAUUUCUAAUUUUUUUAAAAAUUAGAUAAAUGCUGUUGAUGAAGAUUCUUGUCAAUCUUUGUUCACAUCCCUGGCCAUUUCCUUAGGAGAUUGACAUCCGACAGUGGAAUUACUGGAUCAAAGGAUACUGCUUUUAGAGAAUACUGAUAUGUAUUGCUGGUUUGCUCCUUCUUUCAAGCAAUACAUGAAAGUGUCAGUACCCUUACCUGUACUGGUGUAAUUAUAUCUUUUAUUUUUACCAUUUUAUAGGUGAAAUGUGAUAUGUCAUUGUUUUACCAUACUUUGAUAUUAGUGAAGUUAGUGUAUUUUAUGUUUCUCAUCUUUUUACAUCCUUAGACUAUUUAAAAAUUUUUUUUCUUACUAAUUUAUGAGUUAAUUUUUUUUUUUAAAUUGGACAAGUUCUUGCUUUGUCACCUAGGCUAGAGUGCAGUGGUGUGAUCAUGGCUCACUACAGCCUUAACUUCUGGGCUCAAGAGAUCCUCCCACCUCAGCCUCUUGAGUAGCUGGGACUGCAGGUGCACACCACCAUGCCUGGUUAAUUUAAAUUUUUUUUUGUAGAGACUGGUCUUGCUAUGUUGCCAGGGCUGGUCUCUUAAACAGUUGGGCUCAAACAAUCCUCCUACCUCAACCUCCCAAAGUGCUGGUAUUAUAGGCAUGAGCCAUUGUGCCUGGCCAGAGUUUUUAAAAACAUAUUCAGAAUAUUAAUAUCUUGUUUCUCAUUUGUUGCAAAUAAUUUUACCCCCAGCCUUGUUUGUGGUGAUUUUUUUUUUUUGAGACAGAGUCUUGCUCUGUGGUCCAGGCUGGAGUGCAGUGGUGUGGUCUUACUGCAACCUCUGCCUCCUAGGUUCAAACAGUUCUCCCUGCCAAAGCCUCCCAAGUAGCUGGGAUUAUAGGCACCUUUUGUGGCGAUUUUUGAUGCCCAGAGGUAUUUUGUGUGUGUAUGUGUGAUGUCUGUUUUUAAAAUGCUUUGGAAGCUCUUCCUGGUGCUGAGAACAACUCUUUUUCCCCAAGCAGUUAAUUUUGCCAACACUAUUUGGGCAGUUAUGUUUCUCUCUGCUGAUUUGUGAUGUUACCUUUAUUAUAUAUUAAAUUUCUAUGAGUA